AUUCGCGGGAAGGCGUUUGUGGUGCCAGAGAAAAGUAGCCAGAGCGGCGCAGUGGCGGCCGCGUUCUGUGGUUUUCCGCUAUUCCCCCAGACCCGCACCUUCUCGGCCUCUUUGCGGAGAAUCGUGACCAAGAUGUGGAACAGUGGAUUCGAAAGCUAUGGCAGCUCCUCAUACGGGGGAGCCGGCGGCUACACGCAGUCCCCGGGGGGCUUUGGAUCGCCCGCACCUUCUCAAGCCGAAAAGAAAUCAGUAGGUUGAAAGGAGUAUUUAGUUUUGUUUUAUCCUGUCCUGAAGUCCCUGAGUCAUCUAUGACAGAAACUUUAUGCUUUGAAGGAAGAUUUCAACGUGAACUGAUGCGAUAAUGAUCUAUUAUUAUCUGCAUCUCUUAUAAUUAAGUGCUAGAGCCCGAGCCCAGCACAUUGUGCCCUGUACUAUAUCUCAGCUGCUUUCUGCCACUUUGGUUGAUGAAGUGUUCAGAAUUGGGAAUGUUGAGAUUUCACAGGUCACUAUUGUGGGGAUCAUCAGACAUGCAGAGAAGGCUCCAACCAACAUUGUUUACAAAAUAGAUGACAUGACAGCUGCACCCAUGGACGUUCGCCAGUGGGUUGACACAGAUGACACCAGCAGUGAAAACACUGUGGUUCCUCCAGAAACAUAUGUGAAAGUGGCAGGCCACCUGAGAUCUUUUCAGAACAAAAAGAGCCUGGUAGCCUUUAAGAUCAUGCCCCUGGAGGAUAUGAAUGAGUUCACCACACAUAUUCUGGAAGUGAUCAAUGCACACAUGGUACUAAGCAAAGCCAACAGCCAGCCCUCAGCAGGGAGAGCACCUAUCAGCAAUCCAGGAAUGAGUGAAGCAGGGAACUUUGGUGGGAAUAGCUUCAUGCCAGCAAAUGGCCUCACUGUGGCCCAAAACCAGGUGUUGAAUUUGAUUAAGGCUUGUCCAAGACCUGAAGGGUUGAACUUUCAGGAUCUCAAGAACCAGCUGAAACACAUGUCUGUAUCCUCAAUCAAGCAAGCUGUGGAUUUUCUGAGCAAUGAGGGGCACAUCUAUUCUACUGUGGAUGAUGACCAUUUUAAAUCCACAGAUGCAGAAUAACUGGAUCUAACUGGGUACCUGAGAUAUUUUACAGCUGGACCUAGUUUCACAAUCUGUUGUCUCCAGCUCUGCAUAUGUCUGGCCAGGGGGCUUCUAGGAAGUAGGUUUCAUCUAUCAAAUGUCUCCUCUGACUUCCUUUUGAAACUUACUGCUCUUCUGUUUUAUUUUGUUUUGUUUGAAGCUCAGAGGGAGAUGGGCAAUUGACAGGGAUGCAAUCCAGGGUGGGAUUUCUUGAGGAAGUUACAAAUAAGCUUGUUACAACAUCAAGAUAGAUGGAAUUGGAAGGAUGCUACCAGGAGAGUACUUACAUAGUGCUCAGGAGUUUCUCUUCUUAAAAUGUUUACUGCUGAAAGAUGAGCAGGACCAGGGCGUUAUAGGCAGAGCCCUAGCCGAGAAACCUGCUGGCCUCUGCCUGUUUUCAUUUCCCACUUUGGUUGUGUGGCAUUACUUUCAGAAUUGCACUUUCCUGCUUGUCAUGACUUUUUGACACACUUGCCAUGACGUGUGUUUCUGUGAACAUGAAGUUCUGCGGUAGUGCCUCCAGGGGCAGAGGAAAAGAAGAAGUGUUACUGCAUUUUGUACAAAAUAAAUACAGUCAUAUGUUUAAUAAAACAGUUCUAUUGUAGUAACUUGUAAAAA